AGAACGGCGAUGGCAAAAGCAGAUGGAGACGUGAAAAAGUACGGGAGCAAGCGAGGUGAGGACUCCACGGGGACCCCUGUGCUGUUCCCUGUCCCUGAAGCCCACACCUGAGUCCUGCCCAGGGCAGAUGCUUCCACACCCAGGGGGCACCUGAGUCCUACCCAGGGCAGACGCUUCCACACCCUGGGGGCUGGGGGACUGCACCUGGCUCCUGUCUGGGCCCCAGCUUCAUUCCACUGCCCUGGGCCCUGGGAGCUCGGCCGAGCGGGGUCCCCAAGACCUUGCUGCAUUUCUGGGCCUUGGGCUGGGGUGAGGGCCGGGAGAAGGAGCCAGCCUGGAGCCUGGCACGCAGGGAGUGCAUGGCCAGAACCGGUGACAGGCAGGGCUGCCUGCUGGCGUGGAAGAAGUGUCCAUGGCACCCCCAGGCCUGGUUCACAGUGGGAUGGGCGGGGAGCCGGGGGGCUCUGGGGUCCUCGGCUGACCUGCCCCCACCCCUGCCCUGGCUUGUCAGCUCCCAGCAGCAGCCACUCUUGAUGGAUUUUCCAGAAAAUGAGGUGUGGCCAAACAUCUUCAGGCUUUUCCUUCUUUCCUUUCUCCCGUGGCCUGGGUGGGAGCUGCUCCCCAUGCCUGGGGGCAGGUGCGAGAGCCUGUGCCCCUCCCUGGGGCAGUUUCACAGCUGUGUCCCUUCCAGGGGGCCUGCCUGUGUUCACCGUGGCCUCUGCAGCACCUCUCGCCCCUUAGGGCUCCUGCGCCUCGGGUCCCGGUGCCUCAUUUCUCCCUAAAGCAUUGGUUCUGCUGCCGCCGCAGCCGCUGGAAAGUCCCUCCUCAGGUCUAACUGCAGUUCCUCACGGCACAGUGUUCCCCCUCGGGCAUGGUGCUUGGGCAGUGGGUGUGAGUCCAGCUGCCUCACCCUGUCUCGAGAAUGGCCUCUUGCUGGUCUCCCAGCCACCACCCUGUCCCACCCCACGGCGGGGAUGGUGUGGAUGCCUAGCAGCGCGGCUGUGGGCCCACCCAUCCUUAUGGGCAGUGGGGAGCACCUCAGCCCGUGUCCCUACCUUGGUGUAGAGGAGGGGACGGCAGAGAAGCAGGGUUCAGUUAGGGGGGAAGUGGUGGCCCUGCCGGAGGGGCCGUUCCCUGUGUGCCUGGCCCCCAGAUCCUCUCCCCUCCCGGAGCCCAGGGCACAGGCAUAGGCUCUCUGAGUGUCCCACAGCCCCUGGGGGAAGGGAACUGCACCCCCAACCGUGCCCUCCAUCCGCAGAUGGAACGAGAAGCUCCGGGAGCCAGUGCCCAGCGUCUCAUCUGUCUGGGCACCCAGCCCAGAGACGUCUCCCACAACCUGCUCCGGGCGCUGGACGUUGGGCUCCUGGCGAACCUCUCGGCGCUGGCAGAGCUGGAUAUAAGCAACAACAAGAUUUCUACGUUAGAAGAAGGAAUAUUUGCUAAUUUAUUUAAUUUAAGUGAAAUAAACCUGAGUGGGAACCCGUUUGAGUGUGACUGUGGCCUGGCGUGGCUGCCGCGAUGGGCGGAGGAGCAGCAGGUGCGGGUGGUGCAGCCCGAGGCAGCCACGUGUGCUGGGCCUGGCUCCCUGGCUGGCCAGCCUCUGCUUGGCAUCCCCUUGCUGGACAGUGGCUGUGGUGAGGAGUAUGUCGCCUGCCUCCCUGACAACAGCUCAGGCACCGUGGCAGCAGUGUCCUUUUCAGCUGCCCACGAAGGCCUGCUUCAGCCAGAGGCCUGCAGCGCCUUCUGCUUCUCCACCGGCCAGGGCCUCGCAGCCCUCUCGGAGCAGGGCUGGUGCCUGUGUGGGGCGGCCCAGCCCUCCAGUGCCUCCUUUGCCUGCCUGUCCCUCUGCUCCGGCCCCCCGCCACCUCCUGCCCCCACCUGUAGGGGCCCCACCCUCCUCCAGCACGUCUUCCCUGCCUCCCCAGGGGCCACCCUGGUGGGGCCCCACGGACCUCUGGCCUCUGGCCAGCUAGCAGCCUUCCACAUCGCUGCCCCGCUCCCUGUCACUGCCACACGCUGGGACUUCGGAGACGGCUCCGCCGAGGUGGAUGCCGCUGGGCCGGCUGCCUCGCAUCGCUAUGUGCUGCCUGGGCGCUAUCACGUGACGGCCGUGCUGGCCCUGGGGGCCGGCUCAGCCCUGCUGGGGACAGACGUGCAGGUGGAAGCGGCACCUGCCGCCCUGGAGCUCGUGUGCCCGUCCUCGGUGCAGAGUGACGAGAGCCUCGACCUCAGCAUCCAGAACCGCGGUGGUUCAGGCCUGGAGGCCGCCUACAGCAUCGUGGCCCUGGGCGAGGAGCCGGCCCGAGCGGUGCACCCGCUCUGCCCCUCGGACACGGAGAUCUUCCCUGGCAACGGGCACUGCUACCGCCUGGUGGUGGAGAAGGCGGCCUGGCUGCAGGCGCAGGAGCAGUGUCAGGCCUGGGCCGGGGCCGCCCUGGCAAUGGUGGACAGUCCCGCCGUGCAGCGCUUCCUGGUCUCCCGGGUCACCAGGAGCCUAGACGUGUGGAUCGGCUUCUCGACUGUGCAGGGGGUGGAGGUGGGCCCAGCGCCGCAGGGCGAGGCCUUCAGCCUGGAGAGCUGCCAGAACUGGCUGCCCGGGGAGCCACACCCAGCCACAGCCGAGCACUGCGUCCGGCUCGGGCCCACCGGGUGGUGUAACACCGACCUGUGCUCAGCGCCGCACAGCUACGUCUGCGAGCUGCAGCCCGGAGGCCCAGUGCAGGAUGCCGAGAACCUCCUCGUGGGAGCGCCCAGUGGGGACCUGCAGGGACCCCUGACGCCUCUGGCACAGCAGGACGGCCUCUCAGCCCCGCACGAGCCCGUGGAGGUCAUGGUAUUCCCGGGCCUGCGUCUGAGCCGUGAAGCCUUCCUCACCACGGCCGAAUUUGGGACCCAGGAGCUCCGGCGGCCCGCCCAGCUGCGGCUGCAGGUGUACCGGCUCCUCAGCACAGCAGGGACCCCGGAGAACGGCAGCGAGCCUGAGAGCAGGUCCCCGGACAACAGGACCCAGCUGGCCCCCGCGUGCAUGCCAGGGGGACGCUGGUGCCCUGGAGCCAACAUCUGCUUGCCGCUGGACGCCUCCUGCCACCCCCAGGCCUGCGCCAAUGGCUGCACGUCAGGGCCAGGGCUACCCGGGGCCCCCUAUGCGCUAUGGAGAGAGUUCCUCUUCUCCGUUCCCGCGGGGCCCCCCGCGCAGUACUCGCUGCUCCUUCCUGUCUGCCAGGUCUUGGCCUGUGUCCUCUCCCCGUGUGUCCCCCGGUCUGCAACUGUCCUGCCUGUCCUUGUCACGAGCACUGUGGGGAGGCUCCUUGAGGUCACCCUCCACGGCCAGGAUGUCCUCAUGCUCCCUGGUGACCUCGUUGGCUUGCAGCACGACGCUGGCCCUGGCGCCCUCCUGCACUGCUCGCCGGCUCCCGGCCACCCUGGUCCCCGGGCCCCGUACCUCUCCGCCAACGCCUCGUCAUGGCUGCCCCACUUGCCAGCCCAGCUGGAGGGCACUUGGGCCUGCCCUGCCUGUGCCCUGCGGCUGCUUGCAGCCACGGAACAGCUCACCGUGCUGCUGGGCUUGAGGCCCAACCCUGGACUGCGGCUGCCUGGGCGCUAUGAGGUCCGGGCAGAGGUGGGCAAUGGCGUGUCCAGGCACAACCUCUCCUGCAGCUUUGACGUGGUCUCCCCAGUGGCUGGGCUGCGGGUCAUCUACCCUGCCCCCCGCGACGGCCGCCUCUACGUGCCCACCAACGGCUCAGCCUUGGUGCUCCAGGUGGACUCUGGUGCCAACGCCACGGCCACGGCUCGCUGGCCUGGGGGCAGUGUCAGCGCCCGCUUUGAGAAUGUCUGCCCUGCCCUGGUGGCCACCUUCGUGCCCGGCUGCCCCUGGGAGACCAACGAUACCCUGUUCUCAGUGGUAGCACUGCCGUGGCUCAGUGAGGGGGAGCACGUGGUGGACGUGGUGGUGGAAAACAGCGCCAGCCGGGCCAACCUCAGCCUGCGGGUGACGGCGGAGGAGCCCAUCUGUGGCCUCCGCGCCACGCCCAGCCCCGAGGCCCGUGUACUGCAGGGAGUCCUAGUGAGGUACAGCCCCGUGGUGGAGGCCGGCUCGGACAUGGUCUUCCGGUGGACCAUCAACGACAAGCAGUCCCUGACCUUCCAGAACGUGGUCUUCAAUGUCAUUUAUCAGAGCGCGGCGGUCUUCAAGCUCUCACCCGAGGACGCUGCCAUGGCUGUGCUGACGGCCUCCAACCACGUGAGCAACGUCACCGUGAACUACAACGUAACCGUGGAGCGGAUGAACAGGAUGCAGGGUCUGCAGGUCUCCACAGUGCCGGCCGUGCUGUCCCCCAAUGCCACGCUAGCACUGACGGCGGGCGUGCUGGUGGACUCGGCCGUGGAGGUGGCCUUCCUGUGGACCUUUGGGGAUGGGGAGCAGGCCCUCCACCAGUUCCAGCCUCCGUACAACGAGUCCUUCCCGGUUCCAGACCCCUCGGUGGCCCAGGUGCUGGUGGAGCACAAUGUCAUGCACACCUACGCUGCCCCAGGUGAGUACCUCCUGACCGUGCUGGCAUCUAAUGCCUUCGAGAACCUGACGCAGCAGGUGCCUGUGAGCGUGCGCGCCUCCCUGCCCUCCGUGGCUGUGGGUGUGAGUGACGGCGUCCUGGUGGCCGGCCGGCCCGUCACCUUCUACCCGCACCCGCUGCCCUCGCCUGGGGGUGUUCUUUACACGUGGGACUUCGGGGACGGCUCCCCUGUCCUGACCCAGAGCCAGCCGGCUGCCAACCACACCUAUGCCUCGAGGGGCACCUACCACGUGCGCCUGGAGGUCAACAACACGGUGAGCGGUGCGGCGGCCCAGGCGGAUGUGCGCGUCUUUGAGGAGCUCCGCGGACUCAGCGUGGACAUGAGCCUGGCCGUGGAGCAGGGCGCCCCCGUGGUGGUCAGCGCCGCGGUGCAGACGGGCGACAACAUCACGUGGACCUUCGACAUGGGGGACGGCACCGUGCUGUCGGGCCCGGAGGCAACAGUGGAGCAUGUGUACCUGCGGGCACAGAACUGCACAGUGACCGUGGGUGCGGCCAGCCCCGCCGGCCACCUGGCCCGGAGCCUGCACGUGCUGGUCUUCGUCCUGGAGGUGCUGCGCGUUGAACCCGCCGCCUGCAUCCCCACGCAGCCUGACGCGCGGCUCACGGCCUACGUCACCGGGAACCCGGCCCACUACCUCUUCGACUGGACCUUCGGGGAUGGCUCCUCCAACACGACCGUGCGGGGGUGCCCGACGGUGACACACAACUUCACGCGGAGCGGCACGUUCCCCCUGGCGCUGGUGCUGUCCAGCCGCGUGAACAGGGCGCAUUACUUCACCAGCAUCUGCGUGGAGCCAGAGGUGGGCAACGUCACCCUGCAGCCAGAGAGGCAGUUUGUGCAGCUCGGGGACGAGGCCUGGCUGGUGGCAUGUGCCUGGCCCCCGUUCCCCUACCGCUACACCUGGGACUUUGGCACCGAGGAAGCCGCCCCCACCCGUGCCAGGGGCCCUGAGGUGACGUUCAUCUACCGAGACCCAGGCUCCUAUCUUGUGACAGUCACCGCGUCCAACAACAUCUCUGCUGCCAAUGACUCAGCCCUGGUGGAGGUGCAGGAGCCCGUGCUGGUCACCAGCAUCAAGGUCAAUGGCUCCCUUGGGCUGGAGCUGCAGCAGCCGUACCUGUUCUCUGCUGUGGGCCGUGGGCGCCCCGCCAGCUACCUGUGGGAUCUGGGGGACGGUGGGUGGCUCGAGGGUCCGGAGGUCACCCACGCUUACAACAGCACAGGUGACUUCACCGUUAGGGUGGCCGGCUGGAAUGAGGUGAGCCGCAGCGAGGCCUGGCUCAAUGUGACGGUGAAGCGGCGCGUGCGGGGGCUCGUCGUCAAUGCAAGCCGCACGGUGGUGCCCCUGAAUGGGAGCGUGAGCUUCAGCACGUCGCUGGAGGCCGGCAGUGAUGUGCGCUAUUCCUGGGUGCUCUGUGACCGCUGCACGCCCAUCCCUGGGGGUCCUACCAUCUCUUACACCUUCCGCUCCGUGGGCACCUUCAAUAUCAUCGUCACGGCUGAGAACGAGGUGGGCUCCGCCCAGGACAGCAUCUUCGUCUAUGUCCUGCAGCUCAUAGAGGGGCUGCAGGUGGUGGGCGGUGGCCGCUACUUCCCCACCAACCACACGGUACAGCUGCAGGCCGUGGUUAGGGAUGGCACCAACGUCUCCUACAGCUGGACUGCCUGGAGGGACAGGGGCCCGGCCCUGGCCGGCAGCGGCAAAGGCUUCUCGCUCACCGUGCUCGAGGCCGGCACCUACCAUGUGCAGCUGCGGGCCACCAACAUGCUGGGCAGCGCCUGGGCCGACUGCACCAUGGACUUCGUGGAGCCUGUGGGGUGGCUGAUGGUGGCCGCCUCCCCGAACCCAGCUGCCGUCAACACAAGCGUCACCCUCAGUGCCGAGCUGGCUGGUGGCAGUGGUGUCGUAUACACUUGGUCCUUGGAGGAGGGGCUGAGCUGGGAGACCUCCGAGCCAUUUACCACCCAUAGCUUCCCCACACCCGGCCUGCACUUGGUCACCAUGACGGCAGGGAACCCGCUGGGCUCAGCCAACGCCACCGUGGAAGUGGAUGUGCAGGUGCCUGUGAGUGGCCUCAGCAUCAGGGCCAGCGAGCCCGGAGGCAGCUUCGUGGCGGCCGGGUCCUCUGUGCCCUUUUGGGGGCAGCUGGCCACGGGCACCAAUGUGAGCUGGUGCUGGGCUGUGCCCGGCGGCAGCAGCAAGCGUGGCCCUCAUGUCACCAUGGUCUUCCCGGAUGCUGGCACCUUCUCCAUCCGGCUCAAUGCCUCCAACGCAGUCAGCUGGGUCUCAGCCACGUACAACCUCACGGCGGAGGAGCCCAUCGUGGGCCUGGUGCUGUGGGCCAGCAGCAAGGUGGUGGCGCCCGGGCAGCUGGUCCAUUUUCAGAUCCUGCUGGCUGCCGGCUCAGCUGUCACCUUCCGCCUGCAGGUCGGCGGGGCCAACCCCGAGGUGCUCCCCGGGCCCCGUUUCUCCCACAGCUUCCCCCGCGUCGGAGACCACGUGGUGAGCGUGCGGGGCAAAAACCACGUGAGCUGGGCCCAGGCGCAGGUGCGCAUCGUGGUGCUGGAGGCCGUGAGUGGGCUGCAGGUGCCCAACUGCUGCGAGCCUGGCAUCGCCACGGGCACUGAGAGGAACUUCACAGCCCGCGUGCAGCGCGGCUCUCGGGUCGCCUACGCCUGGUACUUCUCGCUGCAGAAGGUCCAGGGCGACUCGCUGGUCAUCCUGUCGGGCCGCGACGUCACCUACACGCCCGUGGCCGCGGGGCUGUUGGAGAUCCAGGUGCGCGCCUUCAACGCCCUGGGCAGUGAGAACCGCACGCUGGUGCUGGAGGUUCAGGACGCCGUCCAGUAUGUGGCCCUGCAGAGCGGCCCCUGCUUCACCAACCGCUCGGCGCAGUUUGAGGCCGCCACCAGCCCCAGCCCCCGGCGUGUGGCCUACCACUGGGACUUUGGGGAUGGGUCGCCAGGGCAGGACACAGAUGAGCCCAGGGCCGAGCACUCCUACCUGAGGCCUGGGGACUACCGCGUGCAGGUGAACGCCUCCAACCUGGUGAGCUUCUUCGUGGCGCAGGCCACGGUGACCGUCCAGGUGCUGGCCUGCCGGGAGCCGGAGGUGGACGUGGUCCUGCCCCUGCAGGUGCUGAUGCGGCGAUCACAGCGCAACUACUUGGAGGCCCACGUUGACCUGCGCGACUGCGUCACCUACCAGACUGAGUACCGCUGGGAGGUGUAUCGCACCGCCAGCUGCCAGCGGCCGGGGCGCCCAGCGCGUGUGGCCCUGCCCGGCGUGGACGUGAGCCGGCCUCGGCUGGUGCUGCCGCGGCUGGCGCUGCCUGUGGGGCACUACUGCUUUGUGUUUGUCGUGUCAUUUGGGGACACGCCACUGACACAGAGCAUCCAGGCCAAUGUGACGGUGGCCCCCGAGCGCCUGGUGCCCAUCAUUGAGGGUGGCUCAUACCGCGUGUGGUCAGACACACGGGACCUGGUGCUGGAUGGGAGCGAGUCCUACGACCCCAACCUGGAGGACGGCGACCAGACGCCGCUCAGUUUCCACUGGGCCUGUGUGGCUUCGACACAGAGGGAGGCUGGCGGGUGUGCGCUGAACUUUGGGCCCCGCGGGAGCAGCACGGUCACCAUUCCACGGGAGCGGCUGGCGGCUGGCGUGGAGUACACCUUCAGCCUGACCGUGUGGAAGGCCGGCCGCAAGGAGGAGGCCACCAACCAGACGGUGCUGAUCCGGAGUGGCCGGGUGCCCAUUGUGUCCUUGGAGUGUGUGUCCUGCAAGGCACAGGCCGUGUACGAAGUGAGCCGCAGCUCCUACGUGUACUUGGAGGGCCGCUGCCUCAAUUGCAGCAGCGGCUCCAAGCGAGGGCGGUGGGCUGCACGUACGUUCAGCAACAAGACGCUGGUGCUGGAUGAGACCACCACAUCCACGGGCAGUGCAGGCAUGCGACUGGUGCUGCGGCGGGGCGUGCUGCGGGACGGCGAGGGAUACACCUUCACGCUCACGGUGCUGGGCCGCUCUGGCGAGGAGGAGGGCUGCGCCUCCAUCCGCCUGUCCCCCAACCGCCCGCCGCUGGGGGGCUCUUGCCGCCUCUUCCCACUGGGCGCUGUGCACGCCCUCACCACCAAGGUGCACUUCGAAUGCACGGGCUGGCAUGACGCGGAGGAUGCUGGCGCCCCGCUGGUGUACGCCCUGCUGCUGCGGCGCUGUCGCCAGGGCCACUGCGAGGAGUUCUGUGUCUACAAGGGCAGCCUCUCCAGCUACGGAGCCGUGCUGCCCCCGGGUUUCAGGCCACACUUCGAGGUGGGCCUGGCCGUGGUGGUGCAGGACCAGCUGGGAGCCGCUGUGGUCGCCCUCAACAGGUCUUUGGCCAUCACCCUCCCAGAGCCCAACGGCAGCGCAACGGGGCUCACAGUCUGGCUGCACGGGCUCACCGCUAGUGUGCUCCCAGGGCUGCUGCGGCAGGCCGAUCCCCAGCACGUCAUCGAGUACUCGUUGGCCCUGGUCACCGUGCUGAACGAGUACGAGCGGGCCCUGGACGUGGCGGCAGAGCCCAAGCACGAGCGGCAGCACCGAGCCCAGAUACGCAAGAACAUCACGGAGACUCUGGUGUCCCUGAGGGUCCACACUGUGGAUGACAUCCAGCAGAUCGCUGCUGCGCUGGCCCAGUGCAUGGGGCCCAGCAGGGAGCUCGUAUGCCGCUCGUGCCUGAAGCAGACGCUGCACAAGCUGGAGGCCAUGAUGCUCAUCCUGCAGGCAGAGACCACCGCGGGCACCGUGACGCCCACCGCCAUCGGAGACAGCAUCCUCAACAUCACAGGAGACCUCAUCCACCUGGCCAGCUCGGACGUGCGGGCACCACAGCCCUCAGAGCUGGGAGCCGAGUCACCAUCUCGGAUGGUGGCGUCCCAGGCCUACAACCUGACCUCUGCCCUCAUGCGCAUCCUCAUGCGCUCCCGCGUGCUCAACGAGGAGCCCCUGACGCUGGCGGGCGAGGAGAUCGUGGCCCAGGGCAAGCGCUCGGACCCGCGGAGCCUGCUGUGCUAUGGCGGCGCCCCAGGGCCUGGCUGCCACUUCUCCAUCCCCGAGGCUUUCAGCGGGGCCCUGGCCAACCUCAGUGACGUGGUGCAGCUCAUCUUUCUGGUGGACUCCAAUCCCUUUCCCUUUGGCUAUAUCAGCAACUACACCGUCUCCACCAAGGUGGCCUCGAUGGCAUUCCAGACACAGGCCGGCGCCCAGAUCCCCAUCGAGCGGCUGGCCUCAGAGCGCGCCAUCACCGUGAAGGUGCCCAACAACUCGGACUGGGCUGCCCGGGGCCACCGCAGCUCCGCCAACUCCGCCAACUCCGUUGUGGUCCAGCCCCAGGCCUCCGUCGGUGCUGUGGUCACCCUGGACAGCAGCAACCCUGCGGCCGGGCUGCAUCUGCAGCUCAACUAUACGCUGCUGGACGGCCACUACCUGUCUGAGGAACCUGAGCCCUACCUGGCAGUCUACCUACACUCGGAGCCCCGGCCCAAUGAGCACAACUGCUCGGCUAGCAGGAGGAUCCGCCCAGAGUCACUCCAGGGUGCUGACCACCGGCCCUACACCUUCUUCAUUUCCCCGGGGAGCAGAGACCCAGCGGGGAGUUACCAUCUGAACCUCUCCAGCCACUUCCGCUGGUCGGCGCUGCAGGUGUCCGUGGGCCUGUACACGUCCCUGUGCCAGUACUUCAGCGAGGAGGACAUGGUGUGGCGGACAGAGGGGCUGCUGCCCCUGGAGGAGACCUCGCCCCGCCAGGCCGUCUGCCUCACCCGCCACCUCACCGCCUUCGGCGCCAGCCUCUUCGUGCCCCCAAGCCAUGUCCGCUUUGUGUUUCCUGAGCCGACAGCGGAUGUAAACUACAUCGUCAUGCUGACAUGUGCUGUGUGCCUGGUGACCUACAUGGUCAUGGCCGCCAUCCUGCACAAGCUGGACCAGUUGGAUGCCAGCCGGGGCCGCGCCAUCCCUUUCUGUGGGCAGCGGGGCCGCUUCAAGUACGAGAUCCUCGUCAAGACAGGCUGGGGCCGGGGCUCAGGUACCACGGCCCACGUGGGCAUCAUGCUGUAUGGGGUGGACAGCCGGAGCGGCCACCGGCACCUGGACGGCGACAGAGCCUUCCACCGCAACAGCCUGGACAUCUUCCGGAUCGCCACCCCGCACAGCCUGGGUAGCGUGUGGAAGAUCCGAGUGUGGCACGACAACAAAGGGCUCAGCCCUGCCUGGUUCCUGCAGCACGUCAUCGUCAGGGACCUGCAGACGGCACGCAGCGCCUUCUUCCUGGUCAAUGACUGGCUUUCGGUGGAGACGGAGGCCAACGGGGGCCUGGUGGAGAAGGAGGUGCUGGCCGCGAGCGACGCAGCCCUUUUGCGCUUCCGGCGCCUGCUGGUGGCUGAGCUGCAGCGUGGCUUCUUUGACAAGCACAUCUGGCUCUCCAUAUGGGACCGGCCGCCUCGUAGCCGUUUCACUCGCAUCCAGAGGGCCACCUGCUGCGUUCUCCUCAUCUGCCUCUUCCUGGGCGCCAACGCCGUGUGGUACGGGGCUGUUGGCGACUCUGCCUACAGCACGGGGCAUGUGUCCAGGCUGAGCCCGCUGAGCGUCGACACAGUCGCUGUUGGCCUGGUGUCCAGCGUGGUUGUCUAUCCCGUCUACCUGGCCAUCCUUUUUCUCUUCCGGAUGUCCCGGAGCAAGGUGGCUGGGAGCCCGAGCCCCACACCUGCCGGGCAGCAGGUGCUGGACAUCGACAGCUGCCUGGACUCGUCCGUGCUGGACAGCUCCUUCCUCACGUUCUCAGGCCUCCACGCUGAGCAGGCCUUUGUUGGACAGAUGAAGAGUGACUUGUUUCUGGAUGAUUCUAAGAGUCUGGUGUGCUGGCCCUCCGGCGAGGGAACGCUCAGUUGGCCGGACCUGCUCAGUGACCCGUCCAUUGUGGGUAGCAAUCUGCGGCAGCUGGCACGGGGCCAGGCGGGCCAUGGGCUGGGCCCAGAGGAGGACGGCUUCUCCCUGGCCAGCCCCUACUCGCCUGCCAAAUCCUUCUCAGCAUCAGAUGAAGACCUGAUCCAGCAGGUCCUUGCCGAGGGGGUCAGCAGCCCAGCCCCUACCCAAGACACCCACAUGGAAACGGACCUGCUCAGCAGCCUGUCCAGCACUCCUGGGGAGAAGACAGAGACGCUGGCGCUGCAGAGGCUGGGGGAGCUGGGGCCACCCAGCCCAGGCCUGAACUGGGAACAGCCCCAGGCAGCGAGGCUGUCCAGGACAGGACUGGUGGAGGGUCUGCGGAAGCGCCUGCUGCCGGCCUGGUGUGCCUCCCUGGCCCACGGGCUCAGCCUGCUCCUGGUGGCUGUGGCUGUGGCUGUCUCAGGGUGGGUGGGUGCGAGCUUCCCCCCGGGCGUGAGUGUUGCGUGGCUCCUGUCCAGCAGCGCCAGCUUCCUGGCCUCAUUCCUCGGCUGGGAGCCACUGAAGGUCUUGCUGGAAGCCCUGUACUUCUCACUGGUGGCCAAGCGGCUGCACCCGGAUGAAGAUGACACCCUGGUAGAGAGCCCGGCUGUGACGCCUGUGAGCGCACGUGUGCCCCGCGUACGGCCACCCCACGGCUUUGCACUCUUCCUGGCCAAGGAAGAAGCCCGCAAGGUCAAGAGGCUACAUGGCAUGCUGCGGAGCCUCCUGGUGUACAUGCUUUUUCUGCUGGUGACCCUGCUGGCCAGCUAUGGGGAUGCCUCAUGCCAUGGGCACGCCUACCGUCUGCAAAGCGCCAUCAAGCAGGAGCUGCACAGCCGGGCCUUCCUGGCCAUCACGCGGUCUGAGGAGCUCUGGCCAUGGAUGGCCCACGUGCUGCUGCCCUACGUCCACGGGAACCAGUCCAGCCCAGAGCUGGGGCCCCCACGGCUGCGGCAGGUGCGGCUGCAGGAAGCACUCUACCCAGACCCUCCCGGCCCCAGGGUCCACACGUGCUCGGCCGCAGGAGGCUUCAGCACCAGCGAUUACGACGUUGGCUGGGAGAGUCCUCACAAUGGCUCGGGGACGUGGGCCUAUUCAGCGCCGGAUCUGCUGGGGGCAUGGUCCUGGGGCUCCUGUGCCGUGUAUGACAGCGGGGGCUACGUGCAGGAGCUGGGCCUGAGCCUGGAGGAGAGCCGCGACCGGCUGCGCUUCCUGCAGCUGCACAACUGGCUGGACAACAGGAGCCGCGCUGUGUUCCUGGAGCUCACGCGCUACAGCCCGGCCGUGGGGCUGCACGCCGCCGUCACGCUGCGCCUCGAGUUCCCGGCGGCCGGCCGCGCCCUGGCCGCCCUCAGCGUCCGCCCCUUUGCGCUGCGCCGCCUCAGCGCGGGCCUCUCGCUGCCUCUGCUCACCUCGGUGUGCCUGCUGCUGUUCGCCGUGCACUUCGCCGUGGCCGAGGCCCGUACUUGGCACAGGGAAGGGCGCUGGCGCGUGCUGCGGCUCGGAGCCUGGGCGCGGUGGCUGCUGGUGGCGCUGACGGCGGCCACGGCACUGGUACGCCUCGCCCAGCUGGGUGCCGCUGACCGCCAGUGGACCCGUUUCGUGCGCGGCCGCCCGCGCCGCUUCACUAGCUUCGACCAGGUGGCGCAGCUGAGCUCCGCAGCCCGUGGCCUGGCGGCCUCGCUGCUCUUCCUGCUUUUGGUCAAGGCUGCCCAGCAGCUACGCUUCGUGCGCCAGUGGUCCGUCUUUGGCAAGACAUUAUGCCGAGCUCUGCCAGAGCUCCUGGGGGUCACCUUGGGCCUGGUGGUGCUCGGGGUAGCCUACGCCCAGCUGGCCAUCCUGCUCGUGUCUUCCUGUGUGGACUCCCUCUGGAGCGUGGCCCAGGCCCUGUUGGUGCUGUGCCCUGGGACUGGGCUCUCUACCCUGUGUCCUGCCGAGUCCUGGCACCUGUCACCCCUGCUGUGUGUGGGGCUCUGGGCACUGCGGCUGUGGGGCGCCCUACGGCUGGGGGCUGUUAUUCUCCGCUGGCGCUACCACGCCUUGCGUGGAGAGCUGUACCGGCCGGCCUGGGAGCCCCAGGACUACGAGAUGGUGGAGUUGUUCCUGCGCAGGCUGCGCCUCUGGAUGGGCCUCAGCAAGGUCAAGGAGUUCCGCCACAAAGUCCGCUUUGAAGGGAUGGAGCCGCUGCCCUCUCGCUCCUCCAGGGGCUCCAAGGUAUCCCCGGAUGUGCCCCCACCCAGCGCUGGCUCCGAUGCCUCGCACCCCUCCACCUCCUCCAGCCAGCUGGAUGGGCUGAGCGUGAGCCUGGGCCGGCUGGGGACAAGGUGUGAGCCUGAGCCCUCCCGCCUCCAAGCCGUGUUCGAGGCCCUGCUCACCCAGUUUGACCGACUCAACCAGGCCACAGAGGACGUCUACCAGCUGGAGCAGCAGCUGCACAGCCUGCAAGGCCGCAGGAGCAGCCGGGCGCCCGCCGGAUCUUCCCGUGGCCCAUCCCCGGGCCUGCGGCCAGCACUGCCCAGCCGCCUUGCCCGGGCCAGUCGGGGUGUGGACCUGGCCACUGGCCCCAGCAGGACACCCCUUCGGGCCAAGAACAAGGUCCACCCCAGCAGCACUUAGUCCUCCUUCCUGGCGGGGGUGGGCCGUGGAGUCGGAGUGGACACCGCUCAGUAUUACUUUCUGCCGCUGUCAAGGCCGAGGGCCAGGCAGAAUGGCUGCACGUAGGUUCCCCAGAGAGCAGGCAGGGGCAUCUGUCUGUCUGUGGGCUUCAGCACUUUAAAGAGGCUGUGUGGCCAACCAGGACCCAGGGUCCCCUCCCCAGCUCCCUUGGGAAGGACACAGCAGUAUUGGACGGUUUCUAGCCUCUGAGAUGCUAAUUUAUUUCCCCGAGUCCUCAGGUACAGCGGGCUGUGCCCGGCCCCACCCCCUGGGCAGAUGUCCCCCACUGCUAAGGCUGCUGGCUUCAGGGAGGGUUAGCCUGCACCGCCGCCACCCUGCCCCUAAGUUAUUACCUCUCCAGUUCCUACCGUACUCCCUGCACCGUCUCACUGUGUGUCUCGUGUCAGUAAUUUAUAUGGUGUUAAAAUGUGUAUAUUUUUGUAUGUCACUAUUUUCACUAGGGCUGAGGGGCCUGCGCCCAGAGCUGGCCUCCCCCAACACCUGCUGCGCUUGGUAGGUGUGGUGGCGUUAUGGCAGCCCGGCUGCUGCUUGGAUGCGAGCUUGGCCUUGGGCCGGUGCUGGGGGCACAGCUGUCUGCCAGGCACUCUCAUCACCCCAGAGGCCUUGUCAUCCUCCCUUGCCCCAGGCCAGGUAGCAAGAGAGCAGCGCCCAGGCCUGCUGGCAUCAGGUCUGGGCAAGUAGCAGGACUAGGCAUGUCAGAGGACCCCAGGGUGGUUAGAGGAAAAGACUCCUCCUGGGGGCUGGCUCCCAGGGUGGAGGAAGGUGACUGUGUGUGUGUGUGUGUGCGCGCGCGCACGCGCGAGUGUGCUGUAUGGCCCAGGCAGCCUCAAGGCCCUCGGAGCUGGCUGUGCCUGCUUCUGUGUACCACUUCUGUGGGCAUGGCCGCUUCUAGAGCCUCGACACCCCCCCAACCCCCGCACCAAGCAGACAAAGUCAAUAAAAGAGCUGUCUGACUGCAA